AAUUUUUUUUUUUUUUUUUUUUGUAGAGACGGAGUCUAACUAUGUUGUCCAGGCUUGUCUUGCCCUUAAUUAUCUUUUAGCUUUUACUUUCUUCCGCCUUUUCCCUCACCUACCCAGGUUGGUUUGAGAUUUGUUUUAGAUAGGCUUCCUGUCCUUAUUGUGAGUAUUUUGAACAUCAGCUGGGCUGUUUGGAUCCCUUUCCUUUAUUUAUUGUUUUUCAGCAACAAACAAGGGUGUGGACUGUGGUGCGAUUAUAGAGCAGCAGACGCUGAGCCGAGCUUGAGACUGGCUGACUUUGUAAAAAAUCAGUCUCUUUGAGUUCAAGGCUGACUUCCUUGGAGAAAAAUUACAGCAGUAUUCGGAAGCUUAAUGUCUCUGUGUUUGAAUGGUUCUCAGACUACCAAAAAACAGACCCUGGGGCCAGAGGCGUGAUGGCAGCUUCUCUUAGAUAAGUCAAGAAUGGUAAAUGCAUGUGUGACUAUCCUCUCCAGUGGUGCAAUACAUUUAUUUAUGUAGAGAUGGAGUUUUUGCUCUGUUGCCCAGGCUGGAGUGCAAUGGCACGAUCUCAGCUCACUGCAACCUCUCCCUCCUGGGUUCACGCCAUUCUCCUGCCUCAGCCUCCUGAGUAGCUGGGAUUACAGGUGUUCGUCCAGCUAAUUUUUGUAUUUUUAGUAGAGGCGGGGUUUCGCUAUGUUGGCCAGGCUAGUCUCAAACUCCCAAUCUCAGGCGAUCCACCCACCUUGGCCUCCCAGAGUUGUAGGAUUACAGGCGUGAGCCACCGCGCCUGGCCUGCAUUUUUAUUUUUUAAGAGAAUAUACAUUUUAAAUUGUUUAUUUUUUUAUGGACAGAACAGUAUGAAGUUAGAGCACAUACCUACUUUGAUACUAGGUGGUAUGCUCUUCCAGCUAGAGCUGCAGGCAGGAUGUGUCUCCUUUAUUGCUGUCCUCUACCUGUCCCACCCAUCCCCAUUCCCCGACUGGGUCCAGCUCAGGCAGAGGGUGGGGGCUGCAGAAAUGCUUGCUGGACAUGGGAAUCGUGGGGUGGUGAGAGGAAUACAGGUUCCAAGUCAGAAGGCCAGGCUUGGAUUAUCGGGUCCAUCAUCUGCUAACCUUGAGCUACUUGUCGUACCUCAUGCCAUCUUUCUGAGCCCGUUUCUUUGCUCUCCAGCUGAUCUCCCAGGAUUCUUGGGAGGUACCAAUGAGAAACUAAAGUGAUGGCAUCGUGAAUGCAGACAUCCUUUGCAGCAUCCAUUUCUCUUUUUCUCUUUUCUUUUUCUUUUUCUUUUUUUUUUUUUAGAGACGGAGUCUCGCUCUGUUGCCCAGGCUGGAGUGCAAUGGGGCGAUCUCGGCUCACUGCAGCCUCCGCCUCCUGGGUUCUAGCAAUUCUCCUGCCUCAGCCUCCCGAGUAGCUGUGAUUACAGGCGCAUGCUGCCACACCCGUCUAAUUUUUUUUUAAAUUUUGGUAGAGACGGGGUUUCACCGUGUUGCCCAGGCUGGUCUCGAACUCCUGAGCUCAGGCAAUCCACCUGCCUCGGCCUCCCAAAGUGCUAAGAUUACAGGCGUGAGCCACCGUGCCUGGCUGCAGCAUCCAUUUCACCUACUUUAUCAAGCACAGGCAGGCUCUGUGUUAGGCAUCGUGGUGAACAACACAGACAUGGUCCUUGCCUUUAUGGAGCUUACCACGAGCUUACCAGCUUACCAGGGAGGGUGAGGGGUGGACAAAGAGAGGAAGCUAAUGAAUGAAUGAAGUUGAUAGUUUCAGAUUGUGGUUAUCGUAGGAGAAUGUGACAGUGUGGAACUGGGAAGGUGAGAUAGGGUGGUACCUCUAGAGGCUGAUGUUUGAGCUGAGGCCUGAAUGAUGAGAAUCUUCCUGAAGCAGAAUUUUAUCCCAAGUGGAUUUUGUUUUCUUUUGUAAAGACAGGGUAUUGCUAUGUUGCCCAGGCUGGUCUCGAACUCCUGGCCUUGAGCAAUCCUCCUGCCUUGGCCUUCCAAAGUUUAGGGAUUACAGGCGUGAGCCCCCGCACCUGGCCCCUAAAUGGAUGUGUUUGCCUCCUGUACUCCUCAGCCUUAUUUGUCACUGUAGCACUGGGCUCCCUCAGCAGUGCAGUGUGUUGGAGACAGUGGCCUCUCUGUGUCCCUAGUUUUGCUACACAUCCCACCUCUCACCGCACCAUUAGUACUCCCAGGAGUCUCCUCCUGGGGACAAAAUCUGUGGAGGAGCCAGACUACUGGCUCUUUGAGAUGAGGAUGAUUUUGUUGACCUCCUGAUAGUUGCUGGGCUCGUAGGACCUUCCUAGCUGAACACAGGUCUGCUAAAGGAGUCCCCCACAUGCCAGGCCCAGUCCUGCUGCAGCUUCUCUCAGCCCCUUGCUGUCUCCCACACUCAGCAGACAUGAAGCACACAGGUCACCUUACUGAGCAAGAUGGUCACAGGCCUGCACCCACGGAGCUUCUGGGCAGGAGCAGCAGGACCAGAGCAUGUGAAAAUGCACAUCUACCACCCAGUCAGAGAGCACUCCGCUGGUCCAGGCGGCAACAUGUCCAUGCUUUUAGUGAUGUCCCUGCCUCUAAUCCAGAAGCCAUGGAGGAGAUAAGGUAGCCCCCCUCGAUCGGAUGGGGAAGCCCAGUUCAAUGGAUACUAAAUUCAAGGAUGACUUAUUUCGGAAGUACGUGCAGUUCCAUGAGAGCAAAGUGGAUACCACCACCAGCAGGCAGCGGCCUGGCAGCGAUGAGUGCCUGCGGGUGGCAGCCUCAACCCUGCUCAGCCUGCACAAGGUGGAUCCCUUUUAUCGAUUCCGGCUGAUCCAGUUCUAUGAGGUGGUGGAGAGCUCCUUGCGCUCGCUCAGCUCCUCUAGCCUGCGGGCUCUGCACGGCGCCUUCAGCAUGCUGGAGACGGUGGGCAUCAACCUCUUCCUCUACCCGUGGAAGAAGGAAUUCAGAAGCAUCAAGACCUACACGGGCCCUUUUGUUUAUUAUGUCAAGUCGACAUUACUGGAAGAGGACAUCCGAGCCAUCCUGAGCUGCAUGGGCUACACACCUGAGCUGGGCACUGCAUACAAGCUCAGAGAGCUCGUGGAGACCCUCCAGGUGAAGAUGGUCUCCUUUGAGCUCUUUCUGGCCAAAGUCGAGUGUGAGCAGAUGCUAGAAAUCCACUCACAAGUGAAGGACAAGGGCUACUCCGAGCUGGACAUUGUGAGCGAGCGCAAGAGCAGUGCAGAGGAUGUGCGCGGCUGCUCGGACGCCCUGCGGCGGCGGGCAGAGGGCCGGGAGCACCUGACGGCCUCCAUGUCACGAGUGGCACUCCAGAAGUCGGCCAGCGAGCGGGCGGCCAAGGACUACUACAAGCCCCGCGUGACCAAGCCCUCGAGGUCAGUGGAUGCCUAUGACAGCUACUGGGAGAGCCGGAAGCCACCCCUGAAGGCCUCAUUGAGUCUUCGGAAGGAGCCUGUGGCAACGGAUGUGGGGGACGACCUCAAGGAUGAGAUCAUCCGCCCAUCCCCUUCGCUGCUGACCAUGGCCAGCUCCCCCCACGGCAGCCCGGAUGUGCUUCCACCCGCCUCCCCCAGCAACGGCCCGGCCCUGCUGCGCGGUACCUACUUCUCCACUCAGGAUGACGUGGAUCUGUACACAGACUCUGAACCCAGGGCCACCUACCGUCGGCAGGAUGCUCUGCGGCCGGAUGUGUGGCUGCUCAGAAACGAUGCCCACUCCCUCUACCACAAGCGCUCGCCCCCUGCCAAAGAGUCCGCCCUCUCCAAGUGCCAAAGCUGCGGGCUGUCCUGCAGCUCCUCCCUCUGCCAGCGCUGUGACAGCCUGCUCACCUGUCCUCCAGCUUCCAAGCCCAGCGCCUUCCCCAGCAAGGCCUCGACUCAUGACAGCCUGGCCCACGGGGCAUCUCUGCGGGAGAAGUACCCAGGCCAGACUCAGGGCCUCGACCGCCUCCCGCACCUUCACUCCAAAUCCAAGCCCUCCACCACGCCCACUUCCCGCUGUGGCUUCUGCAACCGCCCAGGCGCCACCAACACCUGCACCCAGUGUUCAAAAGUCUCAUGUGACGCCUGCCUCAGCGCUUACCAUUAUGACCCCUGCUACAAAAAGAGUGAGCUGCACAAGUUCAUGCCCAACAACCAGCUGAACUACAAGUCCACCCAGCUCUCCCAUCUCGUGUACAGAUAGACCGGCCUCGCCCCUUCCAGCUCCAAGGGCUACAUCAACCGACCUUUCGGGUUUCACGGUGAAGAAGUACUAACGCAUUGAUCUCAGAGGCGGAGGCCUGCACUUGACCAUGUAGGUGGCAGAGAUCGUGGGCUGGCUGUGUCCACGUGGGAGUUCACUUAGCGACUCAGAUAUCUCAACCAAUGGCUGCUUUGUUGUCUGACAAGGGAGAAGGUGGCACUUCCGUUCAGAUUCAUUUUGCUAAUCUCUCCACUCCCUGUUCAGUUGGUUCUUUUUUUGGGGUUUUGUUUUGUUUUGUUUUGUUGUUUUGUUUUUUCCUUUAAAGAGGAUUUCUGUCUCUGGGACCCUCGCUGCACCUACCCCUCCCAUUGCAAAGCCAACUUGGACUGGGAAGGGCCCUUCAGGUCACCAAACAUCCACCUGGAGCGGCGAGCUAGAGGCCUGUUGGCUUGUGAAAUGAGCCCUCCUGCCACACGGGGCCUCUCCCAAAGGCUCAUCCCUUGGCCGCCCCCUUCCUAAACACAAGGAUCCCCAGCUGGACUCCCCACCCCCUGGCUUCCCCACCUCUCCAGGUGUCAAAGGUGAACCGAGUCCAGUAUUAGCUGAAUGUCAUUUCGUACACCACAGCUCAGUCAGCCCAUGGCCUUCGUGAACUUUGCUCCAACACACUGAUGUGUGGGCUUCCCACAGCAGGACUGACUUCCCCCUUUCUGUUGUUUGCACAUGCCCCUCUUACUGUACUGUCAAUAGAUAUUUUUGAGAUUUAUUUUUAAAUAAAUAUUCAACUUGCUGUGUGUUUCAACGUGGUUAAAAAAAUGAAUUAUGUAGCUAUUUAUUAAAUGCCCUGGGUUCUUUAGUCUUCCAAGGGAGGGCCUCGCGCCCAUUCGUGUUGUAUCCUCCACUCACUAUGGCCCGAGGGGAGAGGAGAGUUUGGGGCAGGGAGGAACAGACAUGAAGCCUCCUUUUCUUGAGCUGGUGGAGAGCCACUGUCUUCCCUGCAGUAACUAUCUAUACACCUACCUCCAGUGUGCACUUAGGGGGUGAGCGCGGGUGUCGAGGUCUGUGUGUCUGCAGACUGCUAACCUAUGACAAUUCAGGGACCUCACCUGUCGGACCUAUAGCUUGCUGAGCAGGAACCUUGCACUUCACACUUCUUGAGUCUCGUUUCAGAAGGAAAAUCAUUUGGGAUUCCUACUGCCCCUCCAUCUCAAUCCUCUUCUCUUCACCAGUUUCCAGGACUCAUCUGCAACAUUUGCAAUCUUUUUGCACUAAAAGUGGGCAGGAGUCGGCAUGUGCCCAUCAGAGAGACGGCUCCUCAGAUGCUCAGCUAAGCCUAAGCGCUUCCAAGCCUGAAGGCCCCUUCAGCUUCUCAUGUGAAUUACCAACCCCUGGAUUUUCCUUGUGGGGGUACAAGAGCAGGAGUGGGGCAAGAGUUUGAAAAUAAAGCCGCUUCCUUGUGAACUAACUAUAUUUUAGCCAUAACUGUUUGUGAUGUACACAAUGUUAAGGGAUUUAUAUGCAGUGGGCUUUUCUGGGAGAAAGUUAUUCAGCUCUUGAGCAAGUUUAAGUCUGGCUGAAUCCUGAGGCCACUGUGAAUUUGCUGAUGUUCUUCCAACUCAGUUGAGUGAUUUUAAGGUUUUCCAAAUCUUCUAUGGCUCUCUUUUUAAUAUAUAUAUAUAUAUAUAUAUAUAUAUAUAUAUAUAUAUAUAUAUAUAUCUAUCUGGUAGAUCACAUGUAGAUGUACAGUGUGUAUAUUAAGCUGAAUUUCAACCAACUUUAUUACUAAGACCAGCCUAGCAGGGCAUUCAUCUUUGAUGUUCUUCCUUUUCACAUUUCAGAAUCGGCAAUGCCUGGCCCACUCCUGAGAGCUCUAGUUUUCUAGUUUUCCAUUUCCAGAUUGCGCCAGCAUUACAGUAACUAACUCUUUCUAACCAACCGUGAUGCCACGUAACUUACCCUAUGGACAAAAGCAGGAAUGACUAACACAUCCUAGGAGGGAAAGUCCAGUGUACCUGUCAUCACGGACGCACUGUGGUCACAGACUGGAAUACGAAAUACUACAGCCCUGCUCCCAGGUGUGCAUCUUACUGGAUGAGGUUGCUGUGAUUGAGAUAGUUAAAUACAUGCUAAUUUAAAAAUGCAGAUGUUUUACAUUUGAUUUCUACCAAGAGUUGAAAUGUUGAGAGAUGAUUAAAAAUAAUAAUAAUAAAGUGUCUUCCAUUGUUAAA